GAGUCCAUUUUGGGGCUGUGCUUGGCGCGUACCGUGCGGUCCCUGUAGUUGGAGGACGGGCGGUCGCGCGGCCUUUCCCACUAGCCGGAGGUCGGAGAUAAGUACCCGCCGCCCGGCUCCUCUCGGGAAAGCGGGGUGGUCCUCGAACCUUCAGCGAGGGUGGGGAGUUGCCCAGGUCAGCAGGGAUCUGCGUGGGUUGGGGGGGCUGGCGAAGGCCGUCUGAGCUCCAGUCCGGCAGCGCGGCAGAAACCAGCGGGGCACUGUCAUGGGCCUGGGGAGGAGCGGCCUGCGGAGGGCGCCGGGGCAGUGUGUCUGUGGUCCAGAAAACCUGCUCCGUCCGGAGCCUUCCUGGCCCCGCUACCAGCGUCUCCACAUCCCCUAGAAAAGAAAAGACGGGUGUGGGCCUUAGGUUACAGCGCGCCGCCAGCGUUUGGUUGCAUGGCGCCGGGGGAGGGCGCCCUAACCGAGAAGCUGCUUAAUACAAAGAGCUCCAGGCUCCUGGCGGUUCACCAGGUCUAAACAGCCGGGCUUUAUUUGUGGGGGCGAUUGAAAAAAUUGAGGGUCAAGAUUGGGGUGCUGUGCAAAUAAAUGCGUUAAUACUGUUCUUUUUCUUCUUUCUUUGCAGUAGCCUCUAGUUCGUUAGUCAAAACGUGAAAAAAAAGACCUGCUUUGCCCUGGGAAAUAGUAACCCUGCCAAAUACAUCAGCUUGUAGGAGACAGAGGAUGUGAUGGAGCUGCUUGAAGAAGAUCUCACAUGCCCUAUUUGUUGUAGUCUGUUUGAUGAUCCACGGGUUUUGCCUUGCUCCCACAACUUCUGCAAAAAAUGCUUAGAAGGUAUCUUAGAAGGGAGUGUGCGGAAUUCCUUGUGGAGACCAGCUCCAUUCAAGUGUCCUACAUGCCGUAAGGAAACUUCAGCUACUGGAAUUAAUAGCCUGCAGGUUAAUUACUCCCUGAAGGGUAUUGUGGAAAAGUAUAACAAGAUCAAGAUCUCUCCCAAAAUGCCAGUAUGCAAAGGACACUUGGGGCAGCCUCUCAACAUUUUCUGCCUGACUGAUAUGCAGCUGAUUUGUGGGAUCUGUGCUACUCGUGGGGAGCACACCAAACAUGUCUUCUGUUCUAUUGAAGAUGCCUAUGCUCAGGAAAGGGAUGCCUUUGAGUCCCUCUUCCAGAGCUUUGAGACCUGGCGUCGGGGAGAUGCUCUUUCUCGCUUGGAUACCUUGGAAACUAGUAAGAGGAAAUCCCUACAGUUACUGACUAAAGAUUCAGAUAAAGUGAAGGAAUUUUUUGAGAAGUUACAACACACACUGGAUCAAAAGAAGAAUGAAAUUCUGUCUGACUUUGAGACCAUGAAACUUGCUGUUAUGCAAGCAUAUGACCCAGAGAUCAACAAACUCAACACCAUCUUGCAGGAGCAACGGAUGGCCUUUAACAUUGCUGAGGCUUUCAAAGAUGUGUCAGAACCCAUUGUAUUUCUGCAACAGAUGCAGGAGUUUAGAGAGAAAAUCAAAGUAAUCAAGGAAACUCCUUUACCUCCCUCUAAUUUGCCUGCAAGCCCUUUAAUGAAGAACUUUGAUACCAGUCAGUGGGAAGACAUAAAACUAGUCGAUGUGGAUAAACUUUCUUUGCCUCAAGACACUGGCACAUUCAUUAGCAAGAUUCCCUGGAGCUUUUAUAAGUUAUUUUUGCUAAUCCUUCUGCUUGGCCUUGUCAUUGUCUUUGGUCCUACCAUGUUCCUAGAAUGGUCAUUAUUUGAUGACCUGGCAACUUGGAAAGGCUGUCUUUCAAACUUCAGUUCCUAUCUGACUAAAACAGCCGAUUUCAUAGAACAAUCAGUUUUUUACUGGGAACAGGUGACAGAUGGGUUUUUCAUUUUCAAUGAAAGAUUCAAGAAUUUUACUUUGGUGGUACUGAACAAUGUGGCAGAAUUUGUGUGCAAAUAUAAACUAUUAUAAAAUCUGUUUCAAGUAUGCAGUUUUCUUUUGUUAGAAAUUGUUAGAGAAUAGAGAGUGGUAAUUCAGAUUUGGUCAACGAUUCUAGUCACAUAUUUUCCUCCAAAAGUAUUCCUUCCAAAAAUAAUCUAUACAUGUUCAAAUUAGGUAGCAUAAAGAUAAAAGUGAAAUUUAGUAGUAUAGGCCUGAACCUUUUUUUGUUUAAAAGAGUGCUUUUGAAAUAAGCAUCCACCCCAAAUGUUGGUUGUAUUUAUGCUGUGAUAAAAAUAGGUGAGAGAUCAUAUGAUCUAAUAUUGUAUUGAUGGAAGUAUAGGUAGUAUAGUAGUGAUUGUUCUUCAAGCAUGCAGUAAAGAUCACUUUUUUUUUUUUUUUUUUUUUUGAGAUGGAGUCUUGCUCUGUCGCCCAGGCUGGAGUGCAGUGAUGCAAUCUUGGCUCACUGCAGCCUCUACCUCCCAGGUUCAAGUGAUUAUCCUGCCUUAGCCUCCUGAGUAGCUGGGAUUACAGGCGCGUGCCACCACGCCCAGCUAAUUUUUUGUAUUUUUAGUUGAGACAGGGUUUCACUGUCCCUUAAGACCAUCCUGUUAGCCAAGAUGGUCUUGAUCUCCUGACCUCGUGAUCCGCCUGCCUCGGCCUCCCAAAGUGCUGGGAUUACAGGUGUGAGCCACCGUGCCCAGCCAAAGACUGCUCUUAAAGCACCUUUUUGACAGUGAACAUGGUCUAAAAAAGGGAAGAUAUUGUAGAAGAUUUCACACACACACGCGUGUGUGGGAGACAACUAAAGGUAUUGAAGGUACUAAUUAAUUAGAUUUCCAAAAUUUUCUACAGAGAGUUAAUUAUCACCAAAAUGUGAAUGGUACAUACAAAACCUGGCAUUUUCUUGUGAUAAGUUUACAUUUUUAGGAGAGUGGAGCUUUCAAUCUGCCCUUUUCUCCUUUGUUUUUGUAGUUUUCACCAAAGAUGAUCAACUAGAAAUGUUAAGUGGCUAUGCAAGCAAAAGCAUAGAUAGGUUAAAAAAAAGGAUCAGCUGGCUGGGCAGGGUGGCUCAUGUCUAUAAUCUCAGCAUUCUAGGACAGUGAUGUGGGAGGAUUAUUUGAGGCUAGGAGUUCCAGUUCGAAACCAGCUUCGUAAACAUAGCAAGACCCAGUCUCUACCAAAAAAAAAAAAAAAAAAAAAAAAAAAAAAAAUAUAUAUAUAUAUAUACACACACACACACACAUAUGUACACAUACAUAUAUAUACAUAUAUAUGUAUAUAUAGAACACAUGGCAAGAGCAGGAAAUGGGAAGACUACCUUUUUUCUGGCAGCUAUGUGUUGUUUUGUUCGAAAGAUGGCAAGUGUACAACCAAACCAAUCCACUUGCUUACAGAAAGAAUGUUUAGUGUAGUUAAGACUAAUUUGACAACAGAUAAAACAGUCUGUCAGCUAUUACAAAGUAAUCAGCUGAACACUAAUGCUGUUCUGUCUGCUCACAAGAGAUAAAGAUACCCUCUCAUGGAAUAAACACCUUGCUUAGAAUUCAUAUAACAAAGAAGUAACCUUAUAACUGCUCUCUAGUCUGCCUUAUUUGUGUCAUAGAGUAAGAUAUUCCUUGAAAGCCCAUUAAGUGGAAUAGACUUUCUGAAAAUAAGAGUUCUUUACCUCAGUCCUCCUCUAAUUUGGUUGAGAGGAGGUAAUGAAAAUGGGGACAGGAUAAAAGGUGGCAACUAAAUUUAAAGCACAGAAGAAAUGAUUUCCUUCUAGCUAUGAGAAUAGUCAAAUUGAGCUUGCCAGGCUGUCUCAUUCCUAACAUGUAAUUCAUGAUUUAGCCACUAAAUUUCUAAGGAGAUCAUAAGAAAUUAAGAAAAACGUUUAAGUCUAGCCUCUGCGUGGUAGACAGGUAUGGGGAGGGAGAAUGCUUUUCCCCUCCCAGUAAUAAAAAAAAAAAAAAAAAAAAUAUAUAUAUAUAUAUAUAUAUAUAUAUAUAUAUAUAUAUAUAUAUAUAUAUAUAUAGUUUUACUAGGUUUUCAUGGAUAAGUUUUUAAAUGUAAGACAGGAAAGGGAUCUAUUUGAUGUCUAUCUUCAGAUAUAUUGGCAGUUUUCCUUAAGCUAUUUAGUUCCUCAUCUGUUGCUUUUUCAUUUUGUAUACUGCAAGUUCCCAGGCAACUCGAAUUUGCAAACACAGCCAUGGAUACACUAUUUACCUUACAGUAGUUUCCUGGGAAUCUAAGUCUGGUUUUUGUUAUUCUUCCCUCCCCUCCACUGCAUAAUCAUGUAUAACUAGCAACAUUUAUGGUUAUAGGUUGAUUUCCUAAGUGUGGCUGAUGGUAGCCUCUAGUUUGAAGUGAGGGAAGAAUGAGUAGUCAGGAACUGGUCACUUUGAAUGUGGGAGGGAAGAUAUUCACGACAAGGUUUUCUACGAUAAAGCAGUUUCCUGCUUCUCGUUUGGCACGCAUGUUAGAUGGCAGAGACCAAGAAUUCAAGAUGGUUGGUGGCCAGAUUUUUGUAGACAGAGAUGGUGAUUUGUUUAGUUUCAUCUUAGAUUUUUUGAGAACUCACCAGCUUUUAUUACCCACUGAAUUUUCAGACUAUCUUAGGCUUCAGAGAGAGGCUCUUUUCUAUGAACUUCGUUCUCUAGUUGAUCUCUUAAACCCAUACCUGCUACAGCCAAGACCUGCUCUUGUGGAGGUACAUUUCCUAAGCCGGAACACUCAAGCUUUUUUCAGGGUGUUUGGCUCUUGCAGCAAAACAAUUGAGAUGCUAACAGGGAGGAUUACAGUGUUUACAGAACAACCUUCAGCGCCGACCUGGAAUGGUAACUUUUUCCCUCCUCAGAUGACCUUACUUCCACUGCCUCCACAAAGACCUUCUUACCAUGACCUGGUUUUCCAGUGUGGUUCUGACAGCACUACUGAUAACCAAACUGGAGUCAGGUAUUUUGUACUUUGCAGUAUUUCUCUUGUAUACCAGUUUGUGAUGUUUUCUCUAAAAACUUGAAGUUCCUCAGGCCUGUAACUUCUGGAAAAGAUGAUUAUUCAAAAUAAUGUUUUGGGGUAACCAGUGGAGUUGGGUAGAAUGACCAAAUAAUUAUUUUCCAAACUGGGAUACUUUUUAGAGUGAAAGGGGCUAUUAUUAGGUGGGACAAAAGGAAUAAAUGAAGACUGCCCAGAAAAAACUGAGACUAUGGACAUUCAAAUCAUGGGAGAAAAUAAUUUUGUAGAUUAUGUUCCAUUGCUAAUGAAUUUGACUUAGAAAAGAAUUGCCUUAUUUUUAAGAGAUUGUUUCAGUGGUUCACAUAAAGGCUCGCUCACUGGUUUCUCUUGAGUUCCUUACACACUAUAUAAGUUGUUCUUUCAGUUUUAUGAUUCAACUACUGUUUUUCCUUCAGCUGACUUUAUUUUUAAACACCCUUAAAGACAGAUAUAUCUCAUGGCAAAUUUGGUAUCCUGUUACAGCCUUGGCUCUUAAACAACUCAAAAUAUUGGGAUAGGCUGUCAGUAUGUUAAGGAUAGUUGCUCCUGAGUCAAUUCUUCACUUACUCCCUCUGUUGUUCUUGGCUGGAUCCUAACGCUGAUUUCCACUCUGCUGUCACAAACAUUUUUCCCCCCGUAAAAUGUCUUAAUGCUGUCCUACCAUUAUUUUACCAACUGUGAAAGCUGGCUUUAAUUUUUAGGAGGAAAAGAAAAGCCUGCAUGUGUUCUUUAUUGGUAUCAUUUAAAAUAUACUUUUUUUUUUUUUUUUGGUAAAGGUAGGCGUAUUUUAAGAUAUUUUCUUAACUUGAGCAGUAGCCAACAGGAAGGAUACCAGUGUCUCUCUCUCUUAGCGACACACUCCUUGGUCUUGCUUACCAACUGGAGGACACUAGGUAGAAUAACCGAGUAUGACAAUUCUUAAUUGUUUACAUUUUAUAACUUCCUGUCCUUCAAAAGAGUUUGAAAUGUCAUUUUGGGAAAAGAGAGCCAGUCAAGCUAGUAGGCUGAUUGUGAAGAAAAUCUAAUACCUUAUCUUUAUCUCAAACCUCUGUACAACUUUAUUUUCAUUGAUGGGAUACUUUAACAAAAAUGAAAUUUUUUUUGGUUUUUAAAAUAUGAGUGAUUAUGACCUCUUUGGGGAUCAUGCUUCAAAAAGUCAGAAACCUAGAGACAAAACUGUCAUUGAUUUUUAAGAAGAAACACACUAGGUCAAAAGAAGAUGUCCUGGAAAUACGAAGUACUCUUUAAAAACCAUGCAUUUGGAGAAAGUAAUUGUUUCCUUGAAAAACAUGAUUAAAAACUAAAACUGGGAUGUUCCUGUGUGUACACAGUGCCAAAUGGUUUUCCCUUUUUAUGUUGUGUUUUAGAAACAGCACGAAAGUUUUUUCCAUUUUAAAGUGAGAAAACAUUAUAUUUAGACUUCCAUAAUUCCAAAAUCAGAAGCUAUUUUUAAAAUUAGCAUUUUCUUGCAUCACCAAAUGGUAUUCAAUUGUUUGAAGCUCAAAAUUUUUACCAUUCCAUAAAUGUUUGUGAAUUUUUAGACAGUGCCAAUUUAAAAGUAGAGAUAGCCAAUCUGAAUACGGUGAAAUUAUGGGGAUCUCUGGUGAUUGGGAUGAAAACUCUGGCCUUAAAAGGUCCACUUUUAGUAUAUAAUUGCCUAAUUAGCAAUCAUUUUUAUUUUUUGCUCACUCCCUGGUCUGAAUCUAUCUGUCUAUUCAGAUAUUUUUUGGUAGGUUUGGAAAAUGGAGAAGUGAGCCUAAUUGGUGCCUAAUUGUCUGGUGUAUCAUUCACUUUAUUCAGUUUGUUCUAUCAAUAUGAUUUACCCCUCAAGGUUAACCUAGCAGGUUGCUCAGUUAUUAUCUCUCAAGGUCACAGUACUAGAAAUACUUGGCUUGCAUCUUUCAGAUGCCAUUCAUGUUAUCAAGCUCAAAUUAUAGUUGGUCACAGGAUUCUAAAGUCUUUAUUUGACUUCUCCUUUUUGAACUGGCUCAAAUGGAAAAGUGUAGUUGCUUUUAAAUGUUAAAAAUAAGUUUAAACUUUAUAUUUCCCAUUGGUUUCCCCUAUUUUGUCCUUUCUUUGUGUGCUUGAAAUAUUUUAUUUUUCAGUUUGUCCUCAUAGGGAAUCAAGUAUUUUAGCUAGGUGAUGUCUUGCAAGUACGUUCCACUUUGUUACAAUCUACUAUCUGUAUAUACUAUUUGUAUCUUAAUUCUUUUAUGAGAUGUUCUGUAACAUUUUUCUCACUUUGACAAAUGUUUUUAGACUGUACAGUCAAGAUCUGGCGCUUGGGGGUAAGUGGAAUGAUUUGCUAAUAUUGAGAAUCUGUUGUAUCAAACAUAAUAAACUUUUUUUGAGAUGUG